GAAACAGGAGGAAGCCAGCUCUGUGCCUGGAGGGGACUCGCCGCCAUCUCAGGUCUCUUGGCUUUGCCAGGGCCCACCGGAGAAAACUGACGACCCGUUUCUGUAAUCCUUAUGGGAGACCAACCUUGUGCCUCCGGGAGAUCCACUCUCCCACCUGGAAACGCACGGGAAGCCAAGCCUCCAAAAAAGCGCUGCCUCCUCGCUCCGCGUUGGGAUUAUCCGGAAGGAACUCCCAACGGAGGUAGUACCACUCUACCCUCCGCACCUCCUCCUGCAUCAGCCGGCCUGAAGUCGCACCCUCCUCCUCCGGAGAAGUAGAGAAAUAAAUUUCUCCCACCCUAAACCAGUCUUUGAGUGAUUGCAGUAUGACUCCAUUUCCCUGGUGCAUUCAUAUAAUAGUUCACCUGGUGAAAACAAUGAAGAUUAUUUACAAUGCUACCCUGCUUUUUCUGGUGUCCUGAACCUGGAAGUUGUGCUUUUUAAGUCUUAUGAUGUAAUCAGCGCGAUUUCACUUCCUGAAUUUCGAUGAAUUCUAAGACAUGGGCAAGAUCGGGUUGUAAGACCUCUGAGAUUUAAGGCCAUGCCCUGGAUCAUGGUGAACUUACCAAAGCAAACAAUGCCUGUGAGAUGGUCCUGCAGCAGCCAACCAGUGAACUCUUUUGGUGACAUCCUGUUCUUGUUGUAUAACUUUAUAUUCCUAUAAAUCCAUUAAGGCCCCAAUAAAGUUUGUCUCUAAGCGCUGUGUUAGAUCUAUAUGACUACAUCUAGUAAAUUGUGAAUUUUAAGUAAAUAUUUUAUAAGAACUCCUAUGUAAAGCAUUACUAAAAUUAGUGUUGAAAUAUGACCUUCUUCCUACAUUUAUUCAUUUAUUUAUGUCUAUUUAUUCAUUUAUUUUAGUGAAAAAUAUAAGGAAAGUAGAGGAAGGUUAAAUCCAAAAAAGAAUUGUUUCCAGUACACUUUCUUUAAUUUGCUGUCAGUUUUUGCAUGGAAUCUACAUCUUUUUAUGCUAAUCCUCAUCCUAGUAUUUUACAUCUUAACUAUUUUUUUCUGACUGAAAUGGUUGAUGUGCUUGUUUUUUGUAAUUUUCUACUUUCCUUCUAAAAUGCUUAGUAUUGAACAAAUAGAAUAUCCUAAUUAAAAACAGUAAUAAAUAUUAUGGUGAAAAAAUACAAGUAAAAUGGGAAAACAUUAGAUAGCAGCUUUCAAUAUUUCAUAUAGUUCAUAAAUGUUUCAGGAAUUACAAGGUUAUAGAAAAAAAUUUAUAGACUAUAAUAAUUUCCAGGGAUAUAAAAAAAUAAAGCUUCUACCUUUGAAUUGUAAUAAUAAAAGAUAAACAGACUUGAAAGCAUAUAUUAUAUCUGAAAAUGUCAGAUAAACUUGGCUUAUAAAUUAAAAUAUAAAAUAAUAAUACAAUUUGUUCAAAUAAGUAAUUAAAGCUUACAUUGUAAAAUGAAUAUUUAGAGAGAUUGUGAAACCUGAGUAUUUUACCCAAUCCUCUGAAAUUAGUCCCUAGCAUCAGAAUUAAAGAAUCUGAAAAAUCACAAAUGGAGGUAUGGUGACAUUUAUGUAUAUUCUAGAGUUAUGUUAUGCACACUUAAUAAAUUAUAGACAGUUAUUUUAAAGAUUGUAUAAUAUUACUAAUCACACAUUAGAGUUUUAAAACUUCUGAGCCAGGCUGAACAUCACAAACAGUAAACACAGACUUCUUUAAAAGGACAUCUGGUGAAAGGCAUUUUAUGCAUCAGAAGGCACAGUAUUAUAAAGAUGACAACACUCUUCAAAAUAAUCAAACUAUUCAAUGCAACCCUUAUCAAAAUUAAGGUUGCCUACUUUGAAGAAAUUUAUAACCUGAUUCUAAAGUUCAUAUGAAAAUGUAAUGGACCCAGAAUAGCCAAAACAAUCUUGAAGUAUACAAAGUUUGAAGAGUCACAUUUCCAAAUUUUAAAACUUAUUACAAAGCUACAAUAAACAAGUCUAUGUGGUACUGGCAUAGGAUAUAAAUAUUGAUCAAUGAAAUAGAAUCCAAAGUCCAGACAUAAGCCCUCACAAAAGUUAAUUUGCAGCCAAUUAACUUCUGAGAAGGAGGCAAGACAAAAGGGGAAAUAACUAUUUUCAAUAAAUGGUACUGGGACAACUUGGUAUCUACAUGCAAAAAAAAAACAAAAAAACAAAAAACUUCCACCCCUACCUCAUGCAAAAUACAAAAAUUAACUCAAAAUAGGCCAAAGACUCAAAUAUAAGGGUUACACUAUAAAACUCUUGGGAGGAAAUAUAGAAUAAAUUUUUGUGACCUUGAAUUAAGUAUUAGAUUUUUAAUUCUUACACCAAAGCACAAGUUAAUAAA